GAGGGGGCCAGGCCCGGCGCCUUGGGGUGCCUGUUUAAGUGAGCGCCGAGCGAUCCAGUUGAAGGCAGGGGUGCUUGAAGAGGAAGUGGGGGUGGCUCGCUGCAGGUGUUCUCCCGGGGUCAAAGGUGAAGCCCCGGGCGGUCCACCCCUUCCCAGGCGGCUCUUUUCCGGCAGCUGGUCCUGGUCCCAAGUCUGGAGCAGUUUUCCAAACUGGGAAAUAGUUCCCUGAGUGAGGGAGGGGAGGAGCUUCGGUGGGCCGAGCUAGCCAAAGGGGAAGUCGGCUUUCCCUGGGACUGGCCUGGUUGGACAGCCCCUGGCCAGAGAUCGAGGUCCUGGGAGAAAGAGGGGUGUGUGUACCAAGCCCUGGGUGACAGUGGGCUGGGCAGGGAGGAAGCAGGGGCAGCUCUACCAGGAAACGGCAAAGGGGAGGAAGCAGCCCAGCCUCUCUCCCCAGUUGGCCCUGGAGUCUGGGUUGAGACUGUAGGUGGUGGGAGCUUCAGGGUGCCUAGCCUUGGGGUGCAGCAGAUGGGCUGGUGUGGAUGGCACAGGGUGGCAGAACGCAGCACCCAGCCACCCUAAAGUUGUCGCUACCUGAAGUGGGGUCUCAGCGUUGUGUGAAGUUAGCAAAGGGAGUGGCCCUGUUGGGUGUCUGGCCUGGCAGCCCAGGACGCUUAGAAAGUGGCAGCUUGGGAGUGAUGUGGCCAGAGCCACCUUUCCUUGGGUAUGUGGAGAUUCACGAAGGUUGACUUCCUUUGCCCAGGAGUUCAUUUCAUGGCUGGGUUAGGCUACUUUGUGGUUUGCCCUCAGGGAUGCCCCCCGCCCCCCGCCACACACACACACACACACACACACACACACAGGUCCAUUCUCAGUGAGCACCCCCCACACAUACACACAGAACACAGGUCCACUCUCAGUGAGCCCCGGGGCUUAUAGAUUCCAGAUGUUUCAAUGUUUUAGCUGACCGUUGGCCUGGAGUUUGAUGCCCUGGGAAAAUUUUGGGGUCCUGGAGGGACAUUUAUGUACAUCUUUUUUUUUUUUUUUUUUUGAGACGGAGUCUCACUCUUUUGCCCAGGCUGGAGUGCAGUGGCGCGAUCUCAGCUCACUGCAAGCUCUGCCUCCCAGGUUCACGCCGUUCUCCUGCCUCAGCCUCCCGAGUAGCUGGGACUACAGGCGCCCACCACGACGCCCGGCUAUUUUUUUGUAUUUUUAGUAGAGACGGGGUUUCACCGUGUUAGCCAGGAUGGUCUCGAUCUCCUGACCUCGUAAUCCACCCACCUCGGCCUCCCAAAGUGUUGGGAUUACAGGUGUGAGCCACCGCGCGGCCCAUUUAUGUACAUCUUCUCAGUCACUUAUGCAUCAGUGGAAACUAAGUUUUAGGUUCUGUUCAAAGAGUGACUUUCAGGAGCUGAGAGCUUAUGGAGCAGAGGCCAUGACUGCCGGGGAGUUUCGGCCGCUGGGCUUUGCAGCCAGGUGGGGCUGUCUGUGUUCAGGCACGGGAGUUUCUACUUUAGCCAAAGGAGACGGAGCUCCCAAAUCUCCCUCCCUUUCCUGGCUCUCAGUGUGAAUGGGUGGCCUAGGUACCCUCGCAGGUUGCGGAGCCGUGACCAUCUGUGCCUCCUGCGUGAGGUGGGCUUAUUAGCCUCUGGGAGCAGAGGGUGCAUGACAGGCCCCAGCUCUGCCCAGCCUUGAGGGCUGGAGGAGGGCGGGGGCAGCUUCUCCUCAGUCCAGCUCCUGGGAUCCCUGCAUGGUCCCUCUCAGCCCAGGUCCAGAGGCCAGGCCAGGAGCCUGGAACGCACUGGCUGUGCUCAGGGCUGCCCCUCCCCCACCCCCCGGCGCACCUUUGAUAGGAGGCGAUGGCUUGCACUUGUGCUGAGUUCAGGCCUUCUGCGGAGGGCAAAAUCUGUCGAGGAGGCACUUUUCCGUGUGAUCUCUUCAGGAAGUCACCACUGUCAUUGUGCUUAGCAGCAGGGGUGGGGGCGAUGGGGGUGGGAGAAGCUGGUGCCAGGGCAGUGUCUCUGCACCCUGACUUGCACUCAAGGCUGGGGGGCCCCUCCAUGCUUGGCUGAGGGCCUGUCUCCUGGGGCAGUGUUGUGCCGGACGUGUAGGAAAGGGCUCCUGUGGGCCUUCUGACCUCCAGCUCAGGUCUUCCCCAUCCUUUAUCUGGAAGAAUCCAGUGGCUGGAGCCUCGGGACCUUGCCUCUGAGCUGGCUUGGCUGUGGGGAGGGGUCUCUGGCCUCCCCUCCCUGCUCUGUGCUUGCAGCCUCACCUCCUGGUCCCAGGCUGGGUGAGGUGGAGUCUUGAGCCUGGUGAGGAUGUGUGCAUCCGCCUGGCCACACUUCAGCUCCCCUGAUGAGAGUAAGAAGCCCCCCAGCCCAUAAUUUCCUGAAGUGAUCCUAGCUCCUCUGGAGGAGUCUCCCAUCUGUCUGCAUCAAACCUGGAAAGUGGGGGAUGGAGCAUGAGGCGGGGGUCCAUGCCCAAGGGUCUGGUGGGAGCUGGGCUGAGCUGGGAAUCCCAGAAACAUCCUUAGCAAGAAAGUGAGAGCAGAGUGCUGGAGGGACCCCGAGUGGGGAAGAGUUGGUUGUUAAGUCCGGCCACCCCAGCACUUUUGUUUUUGCUCCCUGGCCCUGUGGGCACUCACCCGGGGCAGGGACCAGAGAGCAGGCUGCAGCUCGGAGGGGCUGACUCCGCCAGCCUUCACGUUGGGCAGGCCCGGGGUGGCUCACUGUGGGAGCCCUUGUGAAAUACCCUGGAUGGGGUGGGGCAGGGGCUGCUUCCUGCAACCCAAAGCCACAGGAUGGUUACUCCAUCAGUGGAGGAGGCCGACUGGGAGGUCUAGAGGGGCCUCGGGCCAGGCUCCUCCCAGCUGAUGGCCUGCCACCUGGAAGGUGGGGGAACUCCCUGGUCAGUCCUGCCAACAGACCAGAGCUAGAUGGACGGCCCACCCCCAGCUUUUCAAAGUUAGGAGGCUGGGAGACUCGGGGUUCCCUGUAGCCUCCUCUCUGGCCAGGUCCCCCGUGGGGCCCCUGUGCACCCAGGGAGCAGGGGGCUUUGUCCGAGGCCGGCUCAGGGGAGGUGGCUGUAGAAGAGAGCGCCUGCUCGCUGUGCCCCCGGGUUAUGACGACCCCCAAUAAAGGAAACAAGGCCUUGAAGGUGAAGCGGGAGCCGGGUGAGAAUGGCACCAGCCUGACGGAUGAGGAGCUGGUGACCAUGUCGGUGCGGGAGCUGAACCAGCACCUGCGGGGCCUGUCCAAGGAGGAGAUCGUCCAGCUGAAGCAGCGCCGGCGCACGCUCAAGAACCGCGGCUACGCUGCCAGCUGCCGCGUGAAGCGGGUGACGCAGAAGGAGGAGCUGGAGAAGCAGAAGGCGGAGCUGCAGCAGGAGGUGGAGAAGCUGGCCUCAGAGAACGCCAGCAUGAAGCUGGAGCUCGACGCGCUGCGCUCCAAGUACGAGGCGCUGCAGACCUUCGCCCGGACGGUGGCCCGCAGCCCCGUGGCGCCAGCCCGGGGCCCCCUUGCCGCCGGCCUGGGGCCCCUCGUCCCAGGCAAGGUGGCCGCCACCAGCGUCAUCACAAUAGUAAAGUCCAAGACGGAUGCCCGAUCGUAGGGACGCGCGUCUGCCCAGGCGGGUCUUUGCGGGGCCACUAGGCACAUGGCGAAUUUGGCUGCCCUGUCCCUCUGUUUCCUUCUCUUCUCUUUCCUCCCUCUCUUCCCCACCCUUCUCUCUUCCCUGCAAAGCACAACCUGUACCCCAGGGGCGCCGGGCUGAGCCCCUUUGAUCUCGUCAUUGUCGUCGUGUGUUUUGUAUGUUGGGAUUGGUCAGUUCGGCGGUGACGUGGGGUCGCCCCAACCCCUUUUGUACCAGGGCCAUGCAGGCUUGGAGUCCAGAGUUGGUGCUGUGGGAACGGACUAGAGAGAGUUGCGGGAGAGAGAAGGAGCAGGCACGCUGGGCCUCGCGUGUCCCCGAGCAGUGAGGGUCCCAGUGUUCCCUCCACUCCCGAGUGGCCACAGGCUCGCGGGCUGGGAAGGAUUCACUCUCUUUAGCCCCAGGGGAGCAGCUCAGCUUAGCCCAGCAUGAAGAGAUGGGCUCUGCUCUGAGAGUAGGGCGGGCUUGAAGGCCCUGAUGGGUGGACCACCAGCCUGGGCGCAGUGGUGCUGGGGGCGUGCAGCUGGGCCCAGGGGCUGUGCACUCAGGCCUGACCCGUUGCACUGAACAAGACCAAAUCUCUGGUUGUGCGCUUAACGUGAGGGUGGGUCCAGUGUGCCCUGCGAUGGGUCCCGUGUCACUGUUUACAUGACCUAUUUGUGUGGUUAUAUAGCCCUUUAUUUAAAAGAGAGAAGUUCCUUUUACAAAGUUAUUAAAUUAAUUAUAUGUUUAAAAGUUAAAGAAAAAAGAGCUGCAGAGUAUUUAUAAAACUGUCUUUUAGAAAAAAAACAAGCAAGAAGACCAUUUGACCAUAUGAAUGGAAAAGGGAAGAAAGUAUAAUAGAAACUUUGCUAGUUAAAAAAAAAAGAAAAAAAAAGAAAAAAAAUCCCUUUCUUGUAAACUUACGGACACCUCUUUGUGGCUGUUGGAGUUUAGUUUUUAUAUACACAGAGUUAUCAGACAUUAUUUAUAAAACUUAGUUUAAAAAAAAGACAAAAAAAAAAAAGCCAAGCCGUGAGCCGACCAGAAGGCCGUCCUCUUUGAUAUCUUUUGCAAUUGUACCGAAAGUGACUUACUCCUCUGCCCUUCCUGCUUCCGUCUCUUGCCGGUGCCGUGGUGUCGUCCGUGCCUGGUGAGGUUUUGUGCAGCGGUAAAGUGCUGGUGCUUCUGGUGACCUUUGACCUGUGGGUGUCACUUCUUGUGUCUGUUUUCCCGUGUUCGUUUUUUGGGUUUAGUUGUGCUUUUGCUUCUGCUGGCUUGCUGGACCUGGGCUGGGGUGCCAAGUGGCGCCUGCUGCGUCAGAGCUCAAGGAAUCUGUGCCCACCACCAGCUCCUGGUCCGUAGGAGGUGAGACAUGGGGUUCUGUCAUGCCCCCCUCCACUGAGCCUUGGCUACAUCUGUGUCUAGGGCUUGGGCUGAUCUAGUGGCGGGGUAGGUGAAACUGGGGUCCCUUGGGGCGCCCCACGCUGCUUCCACACCCACCACCUCUGGCCUUGGGUGGUGGCAUUACAGGGAUGAGGGAGUCACUGUGGGUGGCCACAGGGCUAUGGCCAAGCGUUCCCUGGCCGUCUUCCUCUGGCCUCAGCUUUGUUCCUAUAGGCUGCCCGCGCCGUGGGCUGCAGGUCUCGCCGCCCGCUUGAUCCCUGAGGUGUUUCCAUGCUGCGGGUGGUGCUUCCAGGCAGAGUGGGUGGGGGCCCACCGGGCACCGCCCUUUCUUCCUUGUCCCUGCCUCACUCUGAGAGCCUUGGGGGUCUCCACCAGUGCAGACAAGGGCUACAGUCUCCAGGGCCGGGUCUUGUCCCUCUUCUCCGCUGGUCCACGCUGGCAGCUCUUGGCUUCGGGCCUGCCUUCUGCCUCCCUUUGGGAUCUGUGUCUUCCAGGGAUCAGCUGCUUGGCUUCUGCUGGAGGUGCCUCCCUGUGGGGGCGCAGCCUGCCUCCUGCUCUCAGUUCCUCGCCAGAGGCUGCUGCCCUUCCUGGCUGGGCUCAGGAGGCUCCUUGUAGGCAUAUGAUGGGGAGGGGGUGCCCCUACCCACCUCCAAGAGGCUACAGCCCUGUGUCUGGCCAUGUGAGCCCUGGCCUUUCACCGGGUUGCUGGUUUCUUUUCUGUGGGGCCCAGACUUCUGUAAAGCACACAGAUGUGGGUAAGAUGAAAAACUGUGGCCCAACAGGGCUUAACCCUAUGGAUGGUGGGAUUUUUAUCCAAUAGUUUGGCCUGGUGUGCCCACAGGAUGGGAACAGGGAGGCACCAUCAACACUUGUCAUGUUAAUGAGCUUUUCUUUGCUCGAGGUGUUCAGAGACAAGUCCUGUGUCUACCUGCGUCAGCCUGAAAAUGGAAAUAUUGGCUGUUGACUCUUGUCAUUUAGUGACUUCAUCCCCCUCCCCUCAGUCUGAUCUUGUCUAAGUAGAAUCCAGGCGUUAGUUGGAAUCAUAUCAUAAGUAUCCAUGAAGAAAACGUCAUGAUCUGCCUCGGAGUGGGGAGAAACAGGCCCUCCUUGUCCUUGUGCAGCCCCCACUUUUGUCCUGGCUGUGGGUGGCCAUCCAUUUUGAGCACCUCUGCCAGGCUGCAGACCUGGAGGCGAAGGGAGUGUGGAAGAGGAGGGUGUAAGGGUCGACGCGUGCUGAAUGGGAGGUGCAGGUCCUCGGUGCGUUGGCAGAAGAGGCUUCUGGAGUUUCGAGGCCAUACCUCCUUUCAAGAGCUUUGGAUUUGGGGCGACUUCCCUGGGUCUAGGGGAGUGUUCCUGUCCCCUGUCAGGUCAGCCCUGCGGAGCCACUCCACCCCUCUUCCCCUUCCCCUGGAUUUCCUGACAUAGAUGGUGUGUUCAUGUGCAGGUGUGAGUGUGCUGUCCUUCUGAUCUCUGUUGAUCCCGCUUUCCUACUGAGAGGGUGGUGGAGAGGGUGGUGGUCUCUUCUCACCUCAGUUUUUCUGACACAGCGAAUCGAGGGCUUUGGCCAAGGCCAGGUCUCUCAAACUUGUCCGCCAAGUAAACCAUGAUAUAUGUCUUCCCUUCCACCUUAACUUUGCCCCAACUCCUCUUUUAUCCUAACAUGGACGCUCAGAUUUCAGAGGAAUACCCAGCAGGGACAGGUCAGCUCUCACCAGGAGAGUGAGGCCCCUGGCUGCUGCUCGGGGUGGCACUGGUGUUGCUGGCUCAGCUCUUGGUGCAUGUUUCAGAUAUGUGUGUACACUUCUGACUGGUGAUCAGGGCCCGGCCCACGGCCCUGAGCGGCUGCAGCCUGCUUUGGGACGAUGGUCAGGUCCCAUGUUGUCCCUGCUGCCUCCCUCUGGAGUGGCCACUUGGCCAAAGCGCCCAUCCACAUCUGGAAAGUCGGAGCCGCAGCCUGCUGCACCGUUUCCGCUCUGGGAUCUUGUGAGUUACUUUUUUAGGCUGUGGUUUGGUGAAAGGAACCAACACAUUAACGAUUUUUCCCCCAGAAGCCACUGAAUAAUUCUUUUUGGUGUAUUUUUGCCUUCCUGUUGGCUGUCUGGCCUUGGAGCAGGUCGGGAGAGUAGAGUACAUAAUCAGUGCCACACAGAGGCAGGGCGUGUCUGAGAGACUAAUGCCUGUCCUGCCUCUGGCCUGUGUCCUGGGUGUGUACCAUACCUGCUGGGCCAGUCCCACACAUUUCCACCCUGCCCCUGGAGCAGCAGCUUUGAUACCAUGGGUGUCCCUUGAGUCUGAGCUAGAGUGUGUCCCCGAUAAACUGUGAGACCUCCCUGUUCUUGGUGACCCCAGUUGGGCUUUGGCCCCUCCAGCAACCUUGUGUCCCAGCCCUGCCCUUCUUCCCACCCCCUCAAUCUGCUAGUCCCUGAAGCCUUUAACCAAACGGGAGUGGGCACAGAAAGCCUUCUCCUGGCAACAGGACAAGGGCUGCCCGCGUGUCCAGCCCUGUUGCUCUCCUGGCGCUGAGAGGUGGGUCCAAGCAGAGUUGAUCAGUCCCUGCCUGCCCUGCCUAGGUCUAGCCAGGGGAGGUUGUGUGUGUGGGAGAAGACCCCGGGAUCUGCUGGGGUGGGAUGGAGGUUAUUAAAGAUCUAAGUGAGGAGGGGCUGGGGUUUGGAUGCGGGGUGAGGCCCGAGCGCUCACACUUCGUGUAGGGCGGGCAGGGGCCUGACCUCUUGCAGGGCAGUGGCCUUGGUGCCCUACCCCUGCCCUGCGCAGUAUUUAUUGCUAAAUUAUUGUCCAGGAGGGGCAGCACUGGGCCUGGCCCCCCGGGUAUUUAUUGCUGUACAUAGUGUAUGUUUGUGAUAUAUAAGGUUUUCUUUAUUUUGUAUAUGAUCAAUAAACCUUUUAAAGAGA